GCUGUCGCCGCAGCUCCGGGAGUAGAAGGCGGAGCGGGCGCGCGGAGCGCCUGGCUAGCUCCCUCCCGAUUGCCCGGGGCCGGUUGCGCCUCGGCUGGCGGGGCCGCGGUGAGGAAGGGGCGGCCGCUGCACCCACCUCCACCGGGUUCGUGAGUGGAGCCCAGCCUUAUAUGGACUGAUCGCUCGGGCAAUGGCCCAUUUUUUCCUCGCCACCAGCCGCCACCGCGCGCCGAGCGGCCGCCGGAGCCCGAGCUGACGCCGCCUUGGCACCCCUCCUGGAGUUAGAAACUAAGGCCGGGGCCCGCGGCGCUCGGCGCGCAGGCCGCCCGGCUUCCUGCGUCCAUUUCCGCGUGCUUUCAAAGAAGACAGAGAGAGGCACUGGGUUGGGCUUCAUUUUUUUCCUCCCCAUCCCCAGUUUCUUUCUCUUUUUAAAAAUAAUAAUUAUCCCAAUAAUUAAAGCCAAUUCCCCCCUCCCCUCCCCCAGUCCCUCCCCCCAACUCCCCCCUCCCCCGCCCGCCGGGGCAGGGGAGCGCCACGAAUUGACCAAGUGAAGCUACAACUUUGCGACAUAAAUUUUGGGGUCUCGAACCAUGUCGCUGACCAACACAAAGACGGGGUUUUCGGUCAAGGACAUCUUAGACCUGCCGGACACCAACGAUGAGGAGGGCUCUGUGGCCGAAGGUCCGGAGGAAGAGAACGAGGGGCCCGAGCCAGCCAAGAGGGCCGGGCCGCUGGGGCAGGGCGCCCUGGACGCGGUGCAGAGCCUGCCCCUGAAGAACCCCUUCUACGACAGCAGCGACAACCCGUACACGCGCUGGCUGGCCAGCACCGAGGGCCUUCAGUACUCCCUGCACGGUCUGGCUGCCGGGGCGCCCCCUCAGGACUCAAGCUCCAAGUCCCCGGAGCCCUCGGCCGACGAGUCACCGGACAAUGACAAGGAGACCCCGGGCGGCGGGGGGGACGCCGGCAAGAAGCGAAAGCGGCGAGUGCUUUUCUCCAAGGCGCAGACCUACGAGCUGGAGCGGCGCUUUCGGCAGCAGCGGUACCUGUCGGCGCCCGAGCGCGAACACCUGGCCAGCCUCAUCCGCCUCACGCCCACGCAGGUCAAGAUCUGGUUCCAGAACCACCGCUACAAGAUGAAGCGCGCCCGGGCCGAGAAAGGUAUGGAGGUGACGCCCCUGCCCUCGCCGCGCCGGGUGGCCGUGCCCGUCUUGGUCAGGGACGGCAAACCAUGUCACGCGCUCAAAGCCCAGGACCUGGCAGCCGCCACCUUCCAGGCGGGCAUUCCCUUUUCUGCCUACAGCGCGCAGUCGCUGCAGCACAUGCAGUACAACGCCCAGUACAGCUCGGCCAGCACCCCCCAGUACCCGACAGCACACCCCCUGGUCCAGGCCCAGCAGUGGACUUGGUGAGCGCCGCCCCAACGAGACUCGCGGCCCCAGGCCCAGGCCCCACCCCGGCGGCGGUGGCGGCGAGGAGGCCUCGGUCCUUAUGGUGGUUAUUAUUAUUAUUAUAAUUAUUAUUAUGGAGUCGAGUUGACUCUCGGCUCCACUAGGGAGGCGCCGGGAGGUUGCCUGCGUCUCCUUGGAGUGGCAGAUUCCACCCACCCAGCUCUGCCCAUGCCUCUCCUUCUGAACCUUGGGAGAGGGCUGAACUCUACGCCGUGUUUACAGAAUGUUUGCGCAGCUUCGCUUCUUUGCCUCUCCCCGGGGGGACCAAACCGUCCCAGCGUUAAUGUCGUCACUUGAAAACGAGAAAAAGACCGACCCCCCACCCCUGCUUUCGUGCAUUUUGUAAAAUAUGUUUGUGUGAGUAGCGAUAUUGUCAGCCGUCUUCUAAAGCAAGUGGAGAACACUUUAAAAAUACAGAGAAUUUCUUCCUUUUUUUAAAAAAAAAUAAGAAAAUGCUAAAUAUUUAUGGCCAUGUAAACGUUCUGACAACUGGUGGCAGAUUUCGCUUUUCGUUGUAAAUAUCGGUGGUGAUUGUUGCCAAAAUGACCUUCAGGACCGGCCUGUUUCCCGUCUGGGUCCAACUCCUUUCUUUGUGGCUUGUUUGGGUUUGUUUUUUGUUUUGUUUUUGUUUUUGCGUUUUCCCCUGCUUUCUUCCUUUCUCUUUUUAUUUUAUUGUGCAAACAUUUCUCAAAUAUGGAAAAGAAAACCCUGUAGGCAGGGAGCCCUCUGCCCUGUCCUCCGGGCCUUCAGCCCCGAACUUGGAGCUCAGCUAUUCGGCGCGGUUCCCCAACAGCGCCGGGCGCAGAAAGCUUUCGAUUUUUUAAAUAAGAAUUUUAAUAAAAAUCCUGUGUUUAAAAAAGAAAAAAA